AUUGUGGGCAGAGGGGCGGGGGUUGGGAAGAUGGCGGCUCCCAGCCUCCUCAACUGGAGGCGAGUUUCUUCCUUCACGGGGCCGGUCCCCCGCGCCCGGCACGGACACCGAGCGGUGGCCAUCCGGGAGCUGAUGAUCAUCUUUGGAGGGGGAAAUGAGGGCAUCGCGGAUGAGCUGCACGUCUACAACACGGCUACGAAUCAGUGGUUUCUGCCAGCUGUUAGAGGAGAUAUCCCUCCAGGCUGUGCUGCCCAUGGAUUUGUCUGUGAUGGUACCAGAAUAUUAGUAUUUGGGGGAAUGGUUGAAUAUGGAAGAUACAGCAAUGAGUUAUAUGAGUUACAAGCAAGUCGUUGGUUAUGGAAAAAAGUGAAACCCCAUCCCCCUCCUUCUGGUUUACCUCCUUGUCCUCGGCUUGGACAUAGCUUCUCUUUAUAUGGUAACAAAUGCUAUUUGUUUGGUGGCCUGGCAAACGAAAGCGAAGAUUCAAACAAUAAUGUUCCCAGAUAUUUAAAUGAUUUUUAUGAGUUGGAGCUACAGCAUGGCUCUGGUGUUGUGGGUUGGAGCAUUCCAGUGACUAAAGGGGUUGUGCCUUCUCCAAGAGAAUCCCACACAGCUGUUAUAUAUUGCAAAAAAGAUUCUGGAAGUCCUAAAAUGUAUGUUUUUGGUGGAAUGUGUGGUGCUCGCCUGGAUGACCUAUGGCAGCUUGACUUAGAAACUAUGUCAUGGUCAAAACCAGAAACUAAAGGGACAGUGCCACUUCCACGAAGCCUUCAUACAGCCAGUGUUAUAGGAAACAAGAUGUACAUUUUUGGUGGAUGGGUCCCACAUAAGGGGGAAAAUACUGAGACUUCACCUCAUGAUUGUGAAUGGAGAUGUACCAGUUCAUUUUCUUACCUAAAUCUGGAUACAACAGAGUGGACCACCCUAGUAUCAGAUUCUCAGGAAGAUAAAAAAAAUUCAAGACCAAGACCAAGAGCUGGCCACUGUGCUGUUGCAAUCGGCACUCGAUUGUAUUUUUGGAGUGGAAGAGAUGGCUACAAAAAAGCACUGAAUAGUCAAGUUUGCUGCAAGGAUCUUUGGUAUCUUGAUACUGAGAAACCACCGGCACCAUCUCAAGUACAGCUGAUCAAAGCCACUACCAACUCCUUUCAUGUCAAGUGGGAUGAAGUGUCUACAGUUGAGGGCUAUCUUUUGCAGUUGAGUACAGACUUGCCAUACCAAGCUGCAUCAUCAGAUUCUUCAGCAGCACCAAAUAUGCAAGGAGUCAGGAUGGACCCUCACAGACAAGGCAGUAAUAACAUCGUUCCUAACAGUAUCAAUGAUACAAUAAACAGCACAAAAACUGAACAGCCAGCCACAAAAGAAACUUCAAUGAAAAACAAACCAGACUUUAAAGCACUGACGGAUUCUAAUGCCAUUUUAUAUCCAUCUUUGGCAUCAAAUGCUUCUAAUCAUAAUAGUCAUGUGGUGGAUAUGCUAAGGAAAAAUGAAGGUCCUCACACUUCAGCAAAUGUAGGUGUUCUAAGUAGUUGCCUGGAUGUAAGAACAGUAAUUCCUGAAACAUCUGUAUCCAGUACUGUUUCCAGCACACAAACUAUGGUAACCCAGCAGACCAUUAAAACUGAAUCAUCCAGUACAAAUGGGGCAGUUGUUAAAGAUGAAACUUCACUAACAACAUUCAGUACCAAAUCUGAAGUUGAUGAAACAUAUGCACUGCCUGCAACGAAGAUCAGCCGUGUAGAGACACAUGCUACAGCAACGCCGUUUUCUAAAGAGACUCCUUCAAAUCCAGUGGCCACAGUGAAAGCGGGAGAACGACAAUGGUGUGAUGUGGGAAUUUUUAAAAAUAAUACAGCUUUGGUGAGCCAGUUUUAUUUGCUGCCAAAAGGGAAGCAAAGCAUCUCAAAGGUAGGAAAUGCAGAUGUACCUGACUACAGCUUGCUUAAGAAACAAGAUCUUGUUCCAGGCACAGGAUACAGAUUCAGGGUUGCUGCAAUCAAUGGUUGUGGGAUAGGUCCUUUCAGCAAAAUCAGUGAAUUUAAAACUUGUAUUCCUGGUUUUCCUGGAGCUCCUUCUGCAGUCAGAAUUUCAAAGAAUGUUGAAGGUAUCCACCUUUCCUGGGAACCUCCAACCUCACCUUCUGGAAAUAUUUUGGAAUAUUCAGCCUACUUGGCUAUCCGCACAGCACAGAUACAAGAUAAUCCAAGUCAACUUGUGUUCAUGAGGAUUUAUUGUGGUCUUAAGACAUCAUGUAUAGUAACUGCUGGGCAACUUGCAAAUGCACAUAUUGAUUAUACAUCCAGGCCUGCCAUUGUGUUCAGGAUAUCAGCAAAGAAUGAAAAGGGAUAUGGACCAGCUACACAAGUUCGGUGGCUUCAAGGUAACAAUAAGAAAGCACCUUUAAAUUGAAUUGGUUUUUUUACUGAAGCUAUUGUGAUGAUGAUUAUUUAUUAGUAACUGGUUAUGAAGAUUUGUCAUUUAAAAGAGUAUUCUCUGGCUGUAUUUCCAGCAGUUAUGAACUUGAGUUUGUAAAUUGUUCUUAAAAUGUAUUUGCUGAAUUAUAGAUCCAAAUAAAAGAAAAGAAGCAAAGACUCUCUGAAAAUUAGUAUAUGAGUUCUUCCUUACAGAUAUAGCUCUUUUAUAAAGAAAAACAGUGAAAUUAAGAUAAAAGCUAGAAAGCUUUAUUACCCCAAUAUCUUUUAUAAGGGCUGUGUAACCCAGUCAUCCUAGAGUUAUUGAGAUGAUUCUGGUAACUGGCUGUUGUAUACUAUGCUGUCUUAUAUAGUAAAUGUUCUCUACAUUGUAAAUGUCCUACCUUUGAGUACUCCUUCUAUCUUUAUUCUAUAUGAGCAGUGUUCCUCUAACAACUGUCUUCUAUUGGAUAAUAUGUGUGAUACUAUAAUAAUUCUAAUAGUUAUUUGAUUCCUUUCUUUGUUUACAGUUAGCACAGAGCUUAAGAAAUUAAAAAAGAGGCAAGUUUAGAAACUGCUUUUGAACUUUUAUUAUUUUCCAAGAAUCAUGGUAAAAUACAACAAGAACAAUGAGUUUUCUUGAUUCUUACCAGGCCAAUAUAUUUGAAUAUAUUUUUGGCCAAAGCACUUAACUUAUCUGGCCCUCAUUUUCCUCAUAACAGAUGAGGGAGUUAAAGCAGUUUAUCUUUUAGGUCCCUUUCAGCACUAAGGUUUUGUGUUUUUAGUAGAAGUGAAGUAUGUCCCUGAACAUUUUCAUCUGUCUUAAUGGCUCUAAUUUUGCUUUUGCUAAAAUUAAAAUCUUCAUAAUUGAAUUCAAAAUUAAAGUAUAUGUCCUCCUAUUGGAGAAAAAAACAAGCACCUUAACAGGACACAAGUUUUAAAAUAGUGUUUUAAACAUUUGUAAGAUUUUUGUAAAUGCUCUAAAUGUUUUAUUUUUGCAUUGUUUUUACCUUGAAAUUGUAUAAACUUUUUUACUAUGAAAAUAUAAGCAUUAGACAGCUAACUCAGGUUCCAUUACAACCUUAAAGAUACAGAUAGGCAUUAUAAACACUCUGCUACAGGUAACUUGUUUUAAACCUUUUAGGAAUUUCAUGGUUCCACUGCCUAUUUAAAUCUGGAAUUAAUAUACAGAGCAAUAAUUGCAGAAAAGAUAUUUCAAACUAAGAGCUUCAAUAACUGCAGGGGCACAGGUCUAUCUUUUUUUAUACCACAUAACCUUAUGCCAGUUUAGGUUGACUGAGUAGCUAUGUCCUCAAAUUUCAUGUAUGAUACCCCCCAGCAAAGAUGGAUUUAAUUGUGCAGAAUUGAUAUAUAUGUGUGUUCCAGUUACUAAUUUAAAGUGUAUAGAAUAUUUUAAUAUAUAAUUUUUGUAAAGAACUGGGAUUUUUAUACUACAGUAUUUGUAAUUAAUGUGUCUCACUAAUUAAGUUUCUCUUGAAGAAAAUAUGCAAAUUGUUAGACACAUAAUGAGUGGUUUCCAAACUCUAAAGAUAAAAUAAAUGCACUACUAUGGUGUUGUUAGAAUACCUUUUUUGUGGCUGUAUGAAUCUUUACUCUUUAAAUGUGUACUUUACAAUGUUUACAAGGAGCUUCUCUGGUUUGUUAUCCCAGCAAUGCCCUUGGUGAGAGCUUCAUUCUGCAUUUGUUUAAUUCAUAUGCUUUGCUUUUGGCAUAUGCUUGCUUUUUGCACUAGUAGAAUUUUAACUUACCUCAUUAUUAUGUUUGUAAUCAUUUGUCUAGCUUCUGUAAUGUAUCUGAUAUAGGCUAAACAAAUACUUAACCAAAGUUAAAAUACAUGGUAAGCAAUUUUGCACAUAUUAAAUAUUAGGGUUUGUUGUGUAUAUGUGUAUACUUAAUUAUAAAAGAAUAUGAAUGGAAAGUUAUACUAAAAGUAUAUGUUUCAAGCCCAGUUAUUUUAAAGAUCUAUUGCUUUAAUAGAAAAAGUUUGGCUUUUAACCCUUUCUUCUCUGCAUUAAUUAACAACGUGCAUCUUGAAGCCCUUCUCCUGAUAACAAGGAAUAAGUUGAUUUUAAGCAAAGGAUAGAAUAUUUGUUUGAGUGUGCACAUUUAUACCUGUUUAGUAUUUGAUUCAGUUAAGCCUCCACUCUUCUGGAUCAGGAGGUGAUUCUGAACCUGUGGUUCUAACAUAUGACUUAACUGUUUAGAGGGAAGAGAAGUCUUUCUAUACUGAGGGAUUUGUUAAAAUCAUAAAUGUUUUUGCCCUGAGACUUAGCCCAGAUUCUAUUUUUUUUUUUUUUUUGGCAUUUGUACAUUAAGCACCAGUCAUAUUUAUCUCUGUGAUAAGGGAUUGCUGACUAAAAAAUGCCAUUAAGAAAUCUCUGUGGCUUUGACAUUAGUAGUUAAUAAGAGAUCUUAGAGCUGUGUGCUGAUGAAUAGAAUGAAUUGGAGCAAAUAGCAAGAGAAGUGCAUUUAGCUUCUUAUGAUUUGCACAUUUUCUAAAUGAAGAUCCCUUUGUGUAGCAGUAGGCUGUAUCAUGCAGAUAUUUUUCAUAGGAUUUGCACUGAGUUAAAUGACUUUCUUUACUCUUCCCAGUCAGGUAAGCAGUUCAAAUAUAACAAGACUUUGUGCCAGUCCUCUUCUGUGUUCUGCAACUCUGGCUCUCAUAAGUAGUAAAAAUAUUUUUGAUGUUGCAUGCUCUCAGAAUUAUGUUUUCUAAAAUAUCAUAUUGGCUUCAUUUUAGUUUAAUAAACUUCUUUGGCAACUUAAUUAGACAUAGGGUAUAUAUAAACUCAAUUUUAUCUGCAUUUUUUAAAAAAUUGAAAUAAUCUGAUUGCAUGUAUGAAGGACUCCUGCCUCAUUACCCAAUUACAUAAAUACAAUUAUCUAUAGGAAGGUGAAAUUGUUGAUCUAUUAUUUCAAAGACUUGUAGACUAGCAAAGAUUCAUUCUGAUUAGAAAUAAGGUCUAUAGCUAAAGAUAUUUUUAUUUUAAAAAAUUACAGCCCUUGUAACAAAAAUCAUUUGUAACAUUGGAUAUGAAGACAUUAUUAGUAUUUAAAAUUAUUGUAGUCAUUUGAUCAUAAAUGAAGUAGCUUGCAAAAUAGACUUGGUCUUUGACCCUUUAAGGUGUAACUGACUGACUGUUGUGUUUUUCAAGACUGAUUUUAGGCAGUUUUAUGUAUCGUGUACCAAUGAUAUGUAAAAUAAAGCACCUUUUCUACUAUAAACAA